ACAGUUACAUUUGGCAGGCAGGCGGGCUCGCACGCCGGAGCGCUCAGCCCAGAAUUAGUGGAUUUAUUUGGAAUCUCCCUGCCUCCUCCAAGCUCCGCCGCCGCCGCCGGCUUGUGCAUAGACGGUAGCGUCAAGACACCAGCUGCACUUUGGGUUGCGGACACCCAGAGCCCAGCGCGCCCGCCCUGCGUCUCCGCACCAAGCCCUGUAGCUCCGAGAGGCAUGAACGGAAUCCGGAGGCGCCUGCCUAGCGAGCGAGGACCGGUCGGCGCUUGCCGCCCUCGGGAGCUAACCCCGAGCACCUCCAGCCAUUUGUGAACCUGGAGGCUUGACAUUCGCCAGCGCAGGGCCCCACAAGAGAAAUUUCAAUGAAAAGAAAAGCCAAUGGAUUGUGGUCUUAGAAAAGCUGCUUAGAUGAUGUCUGUUUCCCGUGCUAUAGACACGUGGCAGAGCUGUAAGUAAAUGCUCGGCACUGCAUGAUGAAUUGGAUGGCUGCAGACCGGAGACAAAAAAAAUAAUUGUCUCAUUUUCGUGGUGAUUUGCUUAACUGGUGGGACCAUGCCAGAACGGCUAGCGGAAAUGCUCUUGGAUCUCUGGACUCCAUUAAUAAUAUUAUGGAUUACUCUUCCCCCUUGCAUUUACAUGGCUCCGAUGAAUCAGUCUCAAGUUUUAAUGAGUGGAUCCCCUUUGGAACUAAACAGUCUGGGUGAAGAACAGCGAAUUUUGAACCGCUCCAAAAGAGGCUGGGUUUGGAAUCAAAUGUUUGUCCUGGAAGAGUUUUCUGGACCUGAACCGAUUCUUGUUGGCCGGCUACACACAGACCUGGAUCCUGGGAGCAAAAAAAUCAAGUAUAUCCUAUCAGGUGAUGGAGCUGGGACCAUAUUUCAAAUAAAUGAUGUAACUGGAGAUAUCCAUGCUAUAAAAAGACUUGACCGGGAGGAAAAGGCUGAGUAUACCCUAACAGCUCAAGCAGUGGACUGGGAGACAAGCAAACCUCUGGAGCCUCCUUCUGAAUUUAUUAUUAAAGUUCAAGACAUCAAUGACAAUGCACCAGAGUUUCUUAAUGGACCCUAUCAUGCUACUGUGCCAGAAAUGUCCAUUUUGGGUACAUCUGUCACUAACGUCACUGCGACCGACGCUGAUGACCCAGUUUAUGGAAACAGUGCAAAGUUGGUUUAUAGUAUAUUGGAAGGGCAGCCUUAUUUUUCCAUUGAGCCUGAAACAGCUAUUAUAAAAACUGCCCUUCCCAACAUGGACAGAGAAGCCAAGGAGGAGUACCUGGUUGUUAUCCAAGCCAAAGAUAUGGGUGGACACUCUGGUGGCCUGUCUGGGACCACGACACUUACAGUGACUCUUACUGAUGUUAAUGACAAUCCUCCAAAAUUUGCACAGAGCCUGUAUCACUUCUCAGUACCGGAAGAUGUGGUUCUUGGCACUGCAAUAGGAAGGGUGAAGGCCAAUGAUCAGGAUAUUGGUGAAAAUGCACAGUCAUCAUAUGAUAUCAUCGAUGGAGAUGGAACAGCACUUUUUGAAAUCACUUCUGAUGCCCAGGCCCAGGAUGGCAUUAUAAGGCUAAGAAAACCUCUGGACUUUGAGACCAAAAAAUCCUAUACGCUAAAGGUAGAGGCAGCCAAUGUCCAUAUUGACCCACGCUUCAGUGGCAGGGGGCCCUUUAAAGACACGGCGACAGUCAAAAUCGUGGUUGAAGAUGCUGAUGAGCCUCCGGUCUUCUCUUCACCGACUUACCUACUUGAAGUUCAUGAAAAUGCUGCUCUAAACUCCGUGAUUGGGCAAGUGACUGCUCGUGACCCUGAUAUCACUUCCAGUCCUAUAAGGUUUUCCAUCGACCGGCACACUGACCUGGAGAGGCAGUUCAACAUUAAUGCAGACGAUGGGAAGAUAACGCUGGCAACACCACUUGACAGAGAAUUAAGUGUAUGGCACAACAUAACAAUCAUUGCUACUGAAAUUAGGAACCACAGUCAGAUAUCACGAGUACCUGUUGCUAUUAAAGUGCUGGAUGUCAAUGACAACGCCCCUGAAUUCGCAUCCGAAUAUGAGGCAUUUUUAUGUGAAAAUGGAAAACCCGGCCAAGUCAUUCAAACUGUUAGCGCCAUGGACAAAGAUGAUCCCAAAAACGGACAUUAUUUCUUAUACAGUCUCCUUCCAGAAAUGGUCAACAAUCCGAAUUUCACCAUCAAGAAAAAUGAAGAUAAUUCCCUCAGUAUUUUGGCAAAGCAUAAUGGAUUCAACCGCCAGAAGCAAGAAGUCUAUCUUUUACCAAUCAUAAUCAGUGAUAGUGGAAAUCCUCCACUGAGCAGCACUAGCACCUUGACAAUCAGGGUCUGUGGCUGCAGCAAUGACGGUGUCGUCCAGUCUUGCAAUGUCGAAGCUUAUGUCCUUCCAAUUGGACUCAGUAUGGGCGCCUUAAUUGCCAUAUUAGCAUGCAUCAUUUUGCUGUUAGUCAUCGUGGUGCUGUUUGUAACUCUACGGCGGCAUAAAAAUGAACCAUUAAUUAUCAAAGAUGAUGAAGACGUUCGAGAAAACAUCAUUCGCUACGAUGAUGAAGGAGGAGGGGAGGAGGACACAGAGGCUUUUGACAUUGCAACUUUACAAAAUCCAGAUGGAAUUAAUGGAUUUUUACCCCGUAAGGAUAUUAAACCAGAUUUGCAGUUUAUGCCAAGGCAAGGGCUUGCUCCAGUUCCAAAUGGUGUUGAUGUCGAUGAAUUUAUAAAUGUAAGGCUGCAUGAGGCAGAUAAUGAUCCCACGGCCCCGCCAUAUGACUCCAUUCAGAUAUAUGGCUAUGAAGGCCGAGGGUCAGUGGCUGGCUCCCUCAGCUCCUUGGAGUCCACCACAUCAGACUCAGACCAGAAUUUUGACUACCUCAGUGACUGGGGUCCCCGCUUUAAGAGACUGGGCGAACUCUACUCUGUUGGUGAAAGUGACAAAGAAACUUGACAGUGGAUUAUAAAUAAAUCACUGGAACUGAGCAUUCUGUAAUAUUCUAGGGUCACUCCCCUUAGAUACAACCAAUGUGGCUAUUUGUUUUAGAGGCAAGUUUAGCACCAGUCAUCUAUAAACUCAACCACAUUUUAAUGUUGAACCAAAAAAAGAUAAUAAAAUAAAAAAGUAUAUGUUAGGAGGUUAUAAAUCUUGUGGAGUGUGAAUUAAGUAUGUGGAGUGUCUAGAAGUCCUUGGAUAUUUGAUAUUUACCUGACCACCACAGACAAAGAUUGGGAUCCUGGCUAAUCCUUAGAUAAAUGGUUUAAAUAGAGGAAAAAAUCAUAAUUAAAAGGUGCUUUCUUAGAAAAAAAAAUACGGACCUGCAAGGAAUCUGCUGCUGAUAUGUGUCUUCUGCAAGGAUUUUUAUGAAUGCAAAUGGUUUUUUCCCCUUCACCAAUAAGGAUCCCGCCACAAAUGAUAAAGCAAUACUUGGUCUGCUGUACAUUAUAACUUUUUGGAGUUUUGAGAGGCCUCCUAGAUUAUACAGUACGGUGACCACACAUUGUACAUAAUUGUUGGCCCCACUCACUAGAGACUGAAUAGCAUCUUUAAAUAUUGUGUCGAGCCUUAAAAUAUUCACAUGUUCGUAAUCCAUUCCAGGGUGGGGCUUGCCAAUUCAGUGGUGGGAGGAGAGAAAUCCCAUUCAAACAUGCUUGUUUUCUAGAAGCAGGAUUCCUCGUUCCCUCCUCUUCAUCUUCUUCCACAAGGACACAAAGAUAAACUGUAUCACACAGUGGACUACAUAAGAGACAGAUGGUUUUAUUGCUAGCGCGUGAAUUUAUUUGUUUAAUCCUCGAAAUAAAUAUUUUAUUGAUGUCCAUUAAUGCUUUUAUUUAUUAAGGUCGGUAAUCUAUAGAUUAAGGGGAUAUAUGGGAAAAAACUAAAUUAUAUCCAUUAAUAAUCCUUUAGAUUGUUUUAUAUAAAUAUAUAUACAAUGAAUGUUUAAUACAUGUACAUUUUGAUGAGAUGAGUAUGGCAGGCAAUAUUAUCGAAAGGAGAGCUAAUAGUCUCUUUAGAGUAGAAAGUGUUAUUGUAACUGGAGAUGGCAGGAACAGCAUCUUCCCAGACAAACUUUUGGACUGUUUUCUAUUUUGUUCAUAAUCCUAGUAUUUGGUGUUUUUACUACAAGCACAAACAUCCUAAAGUAUAUUGAUUCCUGUGAAUAUUUAAACUCUAGACUUUUAGAUACCUACAUCAUGCCCUGCCCAAUAAACAUGCUUCAAUUUACCCCCACAGUUUUAGAGCAGGAACUGAUUUGUACAUAAUUUCACUGUUUACGUUUUUAGCACUCCUAUCCCUGAUCUUCAUGGUGAUGCACAGAAUGUCUUAGACUCCAAAAAGGAACAGCACUAGAAGAUGUGAGCAUAUUUAAUUUGUAAUGCAAACCUGCCAUUUAGGAGUAGAAAAUGUAUGAUAAAACUCAAGUAUUACAUGCAGAUCAUUUUAAUUUUCUACUUUGCUUUAAUGCAAUAUUGUUUAUUCACUCCAUGUAUUGUAUUCAGAGAAACUCCUGUAUUGUUUCCUACUUUGUGAAAUAUAUUUUUAUAAAUACCUUUGUUGUCAUUAAUUUUUUUUUCAAUCAGUGGAAGAUCUAUUAACAGAAUCAUCAACUCAAACUAAAAUUCUAGAAUACUCAACCAAAUCAUCCCAAGGGUCACUUUUGUUUGUAAGACUCUUUAUUAUAGAGAAACAGAGAAGAGAAAUGGCUUGCCAGUGAUCACACAGCAAGAUACCAGCAGGGACAUAAGAGGAACAUGGAACACCUAAAGGCUAGUCCAGCUGUGUCAUUUGGGUCCUUCUGGAAGCAGACGCAUUGGGCAGGGAAAACCUUCAGACAAGUUUGCAGACCUAAAACUUGUAACAAUAGAGGGAUUGGGAGCAGGAUUUGGCAAGAGAGUCUUAGACUGCAGUGCGGACCUGGCAAAAUCUCUGCCAGUCUGACAGGGGGUUCUAGAGUGAAAACACAUCCAUUAAAGCAGUCAGGCUGUGGUCCUCUGUCAUCUCAGUCAUUGGUGCGGGGCUGCUAAGAAGAGAACGGUUUUUGACUCAAAAGCUGAACGCACCAACUUCUAGAGGCCACCUUCACUGUGACAGAAACUGCAUGUUUAAAUACUAUACUAACAAUUUAUAACUAUCCGGUGGCUUAAUCAACUUUUUAUUGAGUUUCUGUUGCUGAGAAUAAGUCAUCUUUUAUGCGUAUUAUUACGGCUAGUGAACACUUUUUCUUGAGGUCAAAGGGAUGGUCCAACAUGACUUUAAAAUAUACUAGGACUUGGCACAGUGUCUAAAACAAGUGCUUGGUGAAUGUAAAUUAUUAGUAGUAGUUGCAGUAAUAACCAAUAGUAAUAUUCCAACUAUCUUACACCUUCCAAACCAAGGAGAGAUUAUUAUGUUUUAUGUAUCUCUUGAACACCAGACUCAUUUCUAGUGUACUUUGAAGUGCCCAAAGAUUAUAGACACACAAAUAUGUCUAACAGAAUAAUUACAGUAUUUUUUAAGGAGUAUAAAAUCUGUAUCCUCAAAUAUUGGUAAUCAACAGGAUAAUCUUCGUACAGUGGUUUCUGUGAGCAGGAGAUAAUGUCUGCUCUACUAGUUGCCCAAAUAUCGCCUAAGUAUUCUCUUUGCCUAGGAACACAGAAUGAAAGCUUGCAUCUCUUGCUGACUUUCUUUGCCACCACAGUGUCAGCAUUUUGUGUUUAAAAGCCUAUUUCAGGUCUUGUAACAUAGAAUAAAGUGACUAAUACCUUGAUCCUAAUAAGAUUGACCUAUACUUUUAGAGUGUCAUGAAUUAAACUAAAAAUCUCAGGAACUAUCUCUCUCUUUCUCUCUUUCUCUCUCUCUCUCUCUCUCUCUCUCACACACACACACACACACACACACACACACACACAACAAACAAAUAAAAAACACACAUUUUGACUUGAAGUUUUACUUUAGCAAUAGACUUGCCAGGACUUUCCCAACCAAAAGAUAUCAAUAAGGUUCCUAACAUUUUCUAAGAUUUAAGUAUCCCAUGCUCAAUUUGUUAAAUAACACAUUUUAAAAACUUUAUUGAAAUGACUAUAUUUUUAAAGCUAUGUGCAUUGUUGUCUGUUUCAUCAACAUUGACAUAGCAGAAACAAGAGUACUCUCUGCUAAAUAGAGAAGAAUGAUUAAGUUGGAGCCAAGUGAGACAAAGUUAUCUCCCUCUGCCUACCUCACAAUUCAAGGUUCCCACCUAGGGAACUGAUGCAUCCCUGGGUGAUUGGACACAACAUGGGAUCAAUUCAGCCUCUACUCUGCCUAUGAUUUGAUCAAAUCAUAUUAGCAAAGUGUCUCUUAAACAUCCAUAUAUGAAUAUUAAAGAGUAUUAAGGGGGGCAUUUCUUAACAAUAUUUUUAUGAGUAUAGUUAUAAGUUUCUAAACAUUUAUAAUACGAUGACUAAAAUAUGCUAUUUUUAAAUUCAAGUGUUAACCUUGCCACACAGAAUUAUGACUUCUAGGGUGUAAACUUUAAAGUGAAACUGUUUUGAAAAAAAUCUGCAGUUAAGUGUAUGUGUAUAUAUAGAAGAAAAGGAAACUUAGAUUUACUGGUAUCACCAGUGAAGCAAGAAUGCUUAGAAAGAUACAAAUGUGUCUUUGGGAGAGUCUGCUUAAUCAGAUGCUUAAAGUAAGACAAGUCUCUGCAUGAGACUUAGAAAUCUCCUAGGAGCAGCUGGAUUCCACACUGAGACUCAACAGAGUUCUGGGCUAUGCUGUAUUUUGGAAAAGGAAAAGCGGGUGCUGAGAGCUAAGUAGCCAAUUACUCUUUAUAGCCACAUAAGGACUGAAGGCAAGUAGGCCCUUCCAACAAGUUGUAUUAUGCGAUCACUGGCUUUGCAGGGAAUCUCACGAAUGUAUAACCUUCUGAUUGCCUUUUUGAUUGAAAGUUCCAUCUGAGAUCAGGGCAGUGUAACCAGUAAUAAGAUUUCAAAAAAAUCCCAUCACUGGCACUGUCGGAAAGGCUGAGCAUGACUGAAAUCCUAUCAUUGUCAGUCAAAAAGAUAAGGUAACAGCGGGCAUCACUAUAAAAGCUCUAUAAAUGCACAACUUAAACAUGAAUAUCAACAUUAAAAAGAAUAUAUAUAUCCUUAUACAUAUAUUUAUAAAUAUAUUCAUAUAUAUAAAUAUGCACAUAUAUACACAAUUCAGUUACUGGGGAUAAUUUAUAGUUUUAAUUUUUCAUCUCAUAAUCUCACGCACUGCCAACAAAUUGAAAUUGUGGCUCUCUGUUUUCAUGAAUCUAACCUUGAAUUUGAAAGAAGUUGAAUUGAGGGUAAAGGGUUUUAAAAGCAGCUUUUUAUUUGUGAACAGAAUAAUGGCUCAUAAUACCUGGGAUUAGAAUUAAAUAUGUCACGUUGUGAGGCUGUACUUAGACUUUUUAAAUGUCAUUGUAUUUUUUUGUGGACAAAAUAAUUGUAGAAUAUACUUUGCAGGAAAUACUUUUCUAUAUUUUUUCAAUUUCAAUACUGUUUUAUUUGCUAUAAAAAGUGUCUUUGCACUGUUACUCAGCCAAACAGUGUUGAAUGUAUUAUUUGCCCUUGUAAUUAUUGCUUCUUAUGAUAAUUGUAGAAGAGCAUGUCUUUAUGAUCUAUCAUUUAAAAAUACAUUUAUUGUCAUUGUAGUUUUAGUCAACACAAAUUUAUGGAUUACAUGGUAUACUGUUGCUAUUGAAGAUAUUCUAGUCCUAGUAUUUUGAGCACAGACCUAGCGUUAUGGAGGACAUAAAAUUUAAAAAUUUCCUGACUUGAUGGACUAUCUGAGGAAAAAGAAUUUUGUCUGUCACAUUUAUUGAGUAUCUAUCAGUACAGAAAUUAAGCUACAUGGUUGAUACAGAAAGAUUAAAUACAGUAGCAUUCUCAAACUUAUUUUCUUUAUUUAUAAAAUGUACCUAAUCAAUCUCAUAAGAACUAAUUGUUGAAUUUUUUUUUUAUCUAUGGAUAAAUACUAUUUGAGUCUGGGUUUAAGUUUGGUUGAUCUGACACUAAAUCCCCUUAACUUUCAACUAAACAGUUAUCUCUGUAAUUAUGAGACUUUUGAUGAUAAGAAAUAGAAACUAAGUUAUAUAUAGUGCUAUGGAAGUACUGAGGAGGAAGUAAGGGACCCCAUAUGGGAAGACUCAAGAAGACGUCACGGUGAAAUUUUCCAAAAAGAUGGGAACUCAAGAAUGGGUGCAACAGAAAUCACAGCUUUUCCAAAUACUAAAAGGGAAAAUUAUAAAAAGCACCAAUGGCACACUUUUGGACAUUCAGAAAGAUCCAGAAAUUAGGUGCUUAUAGGAAACUCUAGGUUUGCCAAAUUGUAGUGUUUUAUGGAUAGGAAAAAUGAAGUUCAGAAACGUUAUAAGGAAUUUUCAGGGUUAAAUUACACAUCAAAUAUGUGAGAGAAACAGAAAUUACAUGCUGGUAUUUGGGGUCAUCUCCUGAGUUGUAAUGUUGUAAGUGUUUUUGUAUGUAUUCUCCUCCUUCCUUUAUGUGUGGAAGUUUCAUCUAGGUCUCAAGGUUAGUAGGCAUUUGCUGGUGAAAAUAGUGCCUUUGGGUACUAUUUCCCCAACUUGAGUUACCUGCCACCAUCUAAUUCACAUCUUGAAUGCAAGUAUUAUUUCUUGCAAGUAUCCCUACUAAUAGAUAAUAGAUAUUUCUAUUAUUAUCCACAGAUUACAGAAGAGGGUUGCUAGGAGGAAUAUCACAAGAUGCUGUCUGAAGAGAAAGACUGUGGAAAACCAUGGCUUCAAUGAACUCAGAGGUCAGGACCAGAAAAGGAAAUGAGAGGUCACCAAAGCCAAAUGUUAAUUUCUUGGGAUUUCUUCUGUACAUGCAAAGAACUUCAGGCCAUCCUAUGAUUCCUCAAAAAUAAGAGGAAAAUUUUAACAAUUAUGCUCUAAGAUGGACCAUGACAAUUUAGGAGUCAUUGGGAUCACCCCCCAAAGCCAAAUGUUAAUUUCUUGGGAUUUCUUCUGUACAUGCAAAGAACUUCAGGCCAUCCUAUGAUCCCUCACAAAUAAGAGGAAGAUUUUAACAAUUAUGCUCUAAGAUGGAACAUGACAAUUUAGGAGUCACUGGGAUCACCCCCCCCACCUUUCCAACGUUACUCUGCUUUAACUACAAAUAUGUCGAAUGGUUUUCUAAUUUUUCUUUAACUUAACCUCUAAAGUUCGAGAGCUGUCAUCUUUGUCAAGUCUGAUUGUUGAGUAUGUGAAUGGAUGUUUUUGGCUCAAUGUUAGAGCCAAAAUUUAUAAAUAAUAAUUAUUUAUACAUAAUGAUAUUGCAAAUAAACUUUAAGAAAGAGCUUUAAA